AGAGCGGAGAGGCCUGCGGCGAGGAUGGAGGGCCUGGCAGUGCGGUUGCUGCGCGGCAGCAGGCUGCUAAGAAGAAAUUUCCUGACUUGUUUGUCUUCUUGGAAGAUUCCUCCUCAUGUCUCAAAAUCUUCCCAGUCAGAAGCUCUACUCAAUAUAACAAAUAAUGGAAUACACUUUGCUCCCCUGCAAACAUUUACAGAUGAGGAAAUGAUGAUAAAGAGUUCAGUUAAAAAAUUUGCUCAGGAACAAAUUGCACCUUUGGUUUCAACCAUGGAUGAAAAUUCGAAAAUGGAGAAAUCAGUAAUACAAGGAUUAUUUCAACAAGGGUUGAUGGGUAUUGAAGUUGACCCAGAAUAUGGAGGCACAGGAGCUUCAUUUUUAUCCACUGUGCUCGUGAUAGAGGAAUUAGCCAAAGUUGAUGCAUCUGUGGCUGUCUUUUGUGAGAUCCAGAACACAUUAAUUAACACACUGAUUAGAAAACAUGGAACAGAAGAACAAAAGGCCACCUAUUUGCCUCAGCUCACUACAGAAAAAGUAGGAAGUUUCUGCCUUUCAGAGGCUGGAGCAGGUAGUGACUCAUUUGCUUUGAAGACCAGAGCUGAUAAAGAGGGAGAUUAUUAUGUCCUCAAUGGAUCAAAGAUGUGGAUCAGCAGUGCUGAGCACGCAGGGCUCUUUCUGGUGAUGGCAAAUGUAGACCCUACCAUUGGAUAUAAGGGAAUUACCUCCUUCUUAGUAGAUCGUGAUACUCCGGGCCUUCAUAUAGGGAAACCUGAAAACAAAUUGGGGCUCAGAGCUUCUUCCACCUGCCCGUUAACAUUCGAAAAUGUCAAGGUUCCAGAAGCCAAUAUCUUGGGACAAAUUGGACAUGGCUAUAAGUAUGCCAUAGGGAGUCUCAAUGAAGGUAGAAUAGGAAUUGCUGCACAGAUGCUGGGACUGGCGCAAGGAUGUUUUGACUACACUAUUCCAUAUAUUAAAGAAAGGAUACAAUUUGGCAAAAGACUAUUUGAUUUUCAGGGCCUCCAACACCAAGUGGCUCACGUGGCCACCCAGCUGGAAGCUGCAAGAUUACUAACAUACAAUGCUGCUAGGCUUUUAGAAGCUGGAAAGCCAUUCAUAAAAGAAGCGUCAAUGGCCAAAUACUAUGCAUCAGAGAUUGCAGGACAAACAACGAGUAAAUGUAUCGAGUGGAUGGGGGGAGUAGGCUACACCAAAGAUUACCCUGUGGAGAAAUACUUCCGAGAUGCAAAGAUUGGUACGAUAUAUGAAGGAGCUUCCAACAUCCAGUUGAACACCAUUGCAAAGCAUAUCGAUGCAGAAUACUGACGUCUAUAGGAGUGGGACCCCUCCCUGGUGUCACUGCUGUAAAAUUUUAAACGGUUGUGUCUUGUUGGGAGUAAGUGCCUUGCGUGGGAAUAAACUUCCACAGCAUUCGAAUAUUUUAAUGAAGCCCUUAGUCAGGGUCCUGGUGUUGGCCUUUUUGGUUUUCUCUUUUCAGGCUGUUUAACUUAGGCACAGGAGAUCCACUUUUAAACUUGGGAAAUAAGCACCUGUAUUUUUUUCCAAAACUGUUUUUAAAGCUGUAUACGCAUACAUAUAUAUAUUUUUACUCUGUCUUACUCUGUCACCCAGGCUAGAGUGCAGUGGCGCGAUCUCAGCUCACUGCAGCCUUGACCUCCUGGGUUCCAGUGAUUCUCAUGCCUCAUCCUCCCAAGUAGCUGGAACUACAGGUGUGCACCACCAUGCCUGGUUCAUUUUUGUGUUUUUAGUAGAGAUGGGGUUUUACCAUAUUGCCCAGGCUGGUCUUCUGGCUUCUGGAUAUCGCCCACCUUGGCCUCCCAAAGUGCUGGGAUUACAGGGAUGAGCCACCGUGCCUGGCUGGGUAUUUAUAUUAUCAUUCUAGUUUCAGAGUAUACAGAAGUUUCAUCCCAUCAUUUGGAAAAAUAAAGGCAUCUGAAGUACAAUAUUACUUAUAGAAAUAGUUUAUAUUCCUAUUAAAUCUUAAUCUUGUGGCAUCAGGGAAAUAUUUGUUACAUAGUAGGCAAUUUUUAUCCAGUACUUUAUAGAUUCAACUCUAAGUUGCAAGCGAAGUCAAAACUGAUGAAAAUUUAUUUAGAAAAAUCUAAAAAUUCUGGUUUUAAAUAUGAGAAUCAGUGGAAAAUAAGGGUAUAAUUUUGUAGGUCAUAUGAUUGAAGAAAAUAUUAUUUUAACAAUGUAAAGCAAUAUGAUUUGUUACUAUAAUUAACCUGUAUAAAAGAUACAUUUUAUGGUGGUUUCAGUAGGUCAUUUUAAAAACCAAUGUGCAUUAGUUUUCAAGUAUAAGGUUUAAGUAAUUUGGUUUAAUAAUCAGAAAAUAUUCAAUACAGUGUUGGAUAUUCUGUCAUGCACUAUUUUUCAGUUGACAAUUUCUGUAUUUUAAUUGAAUACUGUUUCUUCAGUCAUGGUUAUUGCACUUUAUCCUGAAUAAUAAUUCAGAAAUUGGGUUUUGGUUCAGUGAUUCUCAAGAAAAAGAUCUCUUGCCCAUUAAGAAGUGUAUCAAAAUCUCAUAAGGAAUGAGGGAGAGAAGGGGGCUGUAGAGUUUGAAAAAGCAUAUUCAAUAUUAAAAUAGUUUUAUAUUUGGGAAGGCAAAAAUGAAUCUAUUGUUUUGCAAUAUAGGUUAUAAACAGGCAAAAUGCAAUAAAAUAUAUAUCUGGUUGUAUUAGUCUGUUUUCACGCUGCUGAUAAAGACAUACCUGAGACCAGGAAGAAAAAGAGGUUUAAUUGGACUUACAGUUCCACAUGACUGGGGAGGCCUCAGAAUCAUGGUGGGAGGCAAAAAGCACUUCUUACAUGGCGGCAGCAAGAGAAAAUGAGAAAGAAGCAAAAGUGGAAACCCCUAAUAAACCUAUCAGAUCUUGUGAGACUUACUAUCACGAGAAUAGCACAGGAAAGACUGGCCCCCAUGAUUCAAUUACCUCCCCCGGGUCCCUCCCACAACACAUGGGAAUUCUGAGAGAUACCAUUUAAGUUGAGAUUUCAGUGGGGACACAGCCAAACCAUAUCAUUCUACCCCUGGCACCUCCAAAUCUCAUGUCCUCACAUUUCAAAACCAAUCAUGCCUUCCCAACAGUCCCCCAAAGUCUUAACUCAUUUCAGCAUUAACCCAAAAGUCCGCAGUCCAAAGUUUCAUCUGAGACAAGGCAAGUCCCUUCCACUUAUGAACCUGUAAAAUCAAAAGUAAACUAGUUACUUCCUAGAUACAAUGGGGGUACAGGUAUUGGGUAAAUACAGCCAUUCCAAAUGGGAGAAAUUGGCCAACACAAAAGGGUAACAGGGCCCAUGCAAGUCCAAAAUUCAGCAGGGCAGUCAAAUUUUAAACCUCCAAAAUGAUCACCUUUGACUCCACGUCUCACAAUCAUCUCUCUCAAGUUCGAAGUUCCACAAAUCUCUAAGGCAAGGGAAAGAUGCUGCCAGUCUCUUUGCUAAAACACAGCAAGAGUCACCUUUACUCCAGUUCCCAAAAAGUUUUUCAUCUCCAUCUGAGACCACCUCAGCCUGAAUUUUAUUGUCAAUAUUGCUAUCAGCAUUUUGGGCAAAGCCAUUCAGCAAGUAUCUAGGAAGUUCCAAACUUUCCCACAUUUUCCUGUCUUCUUCUGAGCCCUUCAAACUGUUCCAACCUCUGCCUGUUACCCAGUUCCAAACUUGCUUUCAUAUUUUUGGCUAUCUUUUCAGCAAUGCCCCACUCUACUGUUAGCAGUUUACUGUAUUAGUCUGUUUUCACACUGCUGAUAAAGACAUUCCUCAAGAUUGUGAAGAAAAAGAGGUUUAAUUGGACUUACAGUUCCACAUGGCCGGGGAGGCCUCAGAAUCAUGGCGGGAGGUGAAAAGCACUUCGUACAUGGUGGUGGCAAGAGAAAAUGAAGAAGAAGCAAAAGUGGAAACCCCUGAUAAACCCAUCAGAUCUCAUGAGACUUACUAUCAUGAGAAUAGCACAGGAAAGACUGGCCCCCCUGAUUCGAUGACCUCCCCCUGGGUCCCUCCCACAACAUGUGGGAAUUCCAGAAGAUAAAUUCAAGUUGCAAUUUCAGUGGGGACAUAGCCAAACCAUAUCACUGGUGAUGCCACUUCUUCAGUAUUAGGGAUUCUCAGUCAGAAGAGACCCCCUGUGUGGCCUGAGUCCCCUCAGGAGGAAGGUGGACAACAGAGAAAUGAGAGUUUUGAUAUUUUCUGAAAGAGGAACAUGUGUUAGAGAUGAAGAAUCUUCCAAGGCUCAUGCAGUUGCUUAGAAUAAUCAUUACUGUUAUAUGAGAAACAUUUUAGUAAUUUAAUAAAAGGAUAAUGUUUAUUUAAAAAACCUGACUUUUCCAGAGUAAUUUUGUUUUGCACAUUCAUGUUUAUUGAAGUGGACUAAUUUCUAUAAUGCAAAUCAGAGUUAAAUAUUAAAAAUUGUGUAAAUACAAUUGACAUAGGAAUUACAUUAAAAUAUUAGGAAGAAACAAGGACAAAUUUAGACCUUGAAUCCGAAGAGAUAAAGCUUACUUGACUUUCAAAUGGAGAGAUGAUGAAAACCCACUCAUUCACUCUUUCAGAACAAAAAGACAGUCAUCUGAUAAGAGUAUGACAUGGAUGAAAUGCCCUACAGGGGCCUUGGACAUCUUUAAUUUCUGCGAUUAUGUGAAAGAGGUGGACUUUACAGAUAAUGGAGCAGAAGCCAACAUUAGUAAAAGGAAUCCCAACUUCUUCCCAUAGAAUUAGAAACAUGUGAAAGUACAAUAAACUUCUUGUUCAAAUUACCAGCAUCAGAGAGCUUCCCAUUUGCAUCUAGACCUUGAAUUUAUAUUUAUUGAUCAAGUUCUAAUUUGUAUGUAUAUUUUGUGCAUAUUCACCAAUAACAGUUAAAAUUAAUUAUGUGUUAUAGUUAAUAUAUGCACCUACCUUCUUCCGUUAGUGCAUCAGUAAAUGUGUUAUUUUGUCAUUUUUCCAAAGAGAGUGUUGUAGGUUUUCCCUGUAGUUCUUCCUUUAUAGCUUUUCUUCUGAUAACCAUGACUUCAGGAGCUUUAAAACUAUCUAUCUUGCAUUUGUGUCUGGCGGAGAACUAGCCAUCAGCCUCCUGAAGCCUGCCAUCAUUGUUAAUUUGAGGACUGGGCUGUCUUGGGGCUCAGAAGAUAAAGAACUAUUUGAGCAGAUGUGUGUGGGUGGCACUGGAUUCCACCCAACUGCCAAGUUAGUAUUGUUAGAGAUUUCAUUUUACAACACAAAAAUAAGCCUGUGUCAAAGAUUUUAAAAUCAUGGAAAGUUAAAAUCUAGAAAGACCUUAGAGAACCAGCCAACCAACUCUCUCAUUUUAAAAGUGAAGGAUUCAUAGCACAGAUUACUUGCCUAAGAUCAUCCAGGAACGAAGACAAGAAUCCAAAUGUACUUGGGGACAAGAAUUAGUCCCCAAAUUCAGUGUUCUUCCUAGUAUUAAACAUUGCCCCUUUCGACAAAUUUUGGAUUUCAUUCUUGUUAUAUUUCAGUACUCUUGCUGAUUUAUUUUAGGUUUAACUGGUAAAGAAUGAACAUUUCAGAAGUGUUAGGAUUAGUCAGUGUCAUCGCUUAUGUAUAUGAAUCACUUGCCAAAGACACUGGCUCUCCUCAGCUGUAACCAGCAUGUCAAAUGUGAAGAUUAUUGUGUGGGAUCCUUUGGUUUCAUUGUUAUGAUGUAUUUUAUAAAUGUACUAGUUAUAUCCUUGUUUAUGUAUUUUUGCUGAUCUUUCAUAAAGCAGAAUGGUAUGUAUCGGAUUGUUUUAAUGUUAUAUAUUGGAUUGUAUUCGAUGUUACAAAACCAAUAUUCUAUGGAGAAUGAAAAAAAUAAAGGACUAAAUUAACUGGA